GCAGUGUGCGUCCGCGUCUGAGGGGAGGGAUGUGGGGGAAGCGACGGCCCCCGGUUUGUUUGGGCUGUGGGCGGUGCGCAGCGGAGAGCCCGGGAAAAGCGGGAAAUGGCGGCGCCGAGCGCGGGGUCUUGGUCCACCUUCCAGCACAAGGAGCUGAUGGCCGCUGACAGGGGACGCAGGAUAUUGGGAGUGUGUGGCAUGCAUCCUCAUCAUCAGGAAACUCUAAAAAAGAACCGAGUGGUGCUAGCCAAACAGCUGUUGUUGAGCGAAUUGUUAGAACAUCUUCUGGAGAAGGACAUCAUCACCUUGGAAAUGAGGGAGCUCAUCCAGGCCAAAGUGGGCAGUUUCAGCCAGAAUGUGGAACUCCUCAACUUGCUGCCUAAGAGGGGUCCCCAAGCUUUUGAUGCCUUCUGUGAAGCACUGAGGGAGACCAAGCAAGGCCACCUGGAGGAUAUGUUGCUCACCACCCUUUCUGGGCUUCAGCAUGUACUCCCACCGUUGAGCUGUGACUACGACUUGAGUCUCCCUUUUCCGGUGUGUGAGUCCUGUCCCCUUUACAAGAAGCUCCGCCUGUCGACAGAUACUGUGGAACACUCCCUAGACAAUAAAGAUGGUCCUGUCUGCCUUCAGGUGAAGCCUUGCACUCCUGAAUUUUAUCAAACACACUUCCAGCUGGCAUAUAGGUUGCAGUCUCGGCCUCGUGGCCUAGCACUGGUGUUGAGCAAUGUGCACUUCACUGGAGAGAAAGAACUGGAAUUUCGCUCUGGAGGGGAUGUGGACCACAGUACUCUAGUCACCCUCUUCAAGCUUUUGGGCUAUGACGUCCAUGUUCUAUGUGACCAGACUGCACAGGAAAUGCAAGAGAAACUGCAGAAUUUUGCACAGUUACCUGCACACCGAGUCACGGACUCCUGCAUCGUGGCACUCCUCUCGCAUGGUGUGGAGGGCGCCAUCUAUGGUGUGGAUGGGAAACUGCUCCAGCUCCAAGAGGUUUUUCAGCUCUUUGACAACGCCAACUGCCCAAGCCUACAGAACAAACCAAAAAUGUUCUUCAUCCAGGCCUGCCGUGGAGAUGAGACUGAUCGUGGGGUUGACCAACAAGAUGGAAAGAACCACGCAGGAUCCCCUGGGUGCGAGGAGAGUGAUGCCGGUAAAGAAAAGUUGCCGAAGAUGAGACUGCCCACGCGCUCAGACAUGAUAUGCGGCUAUGCCUGCCUCAAAGGGACUGCCGCCAUGCGGAACACCAAACGAGGUUCCUGGUACAUCGAGGCUCUUGCUCAAGUGUUUUCUGAGCGGGCUUGUGAUAUGCACGUGGCCGACAUGCUGGUUAAGGUGAACGCACUUAUCAAGGAUCGGGAAGGUUAUGCUCCUGGCACAGAAUUCCACCGGUGCAAGGAGAUGUCUGAAUACUGCAGCACUCUGUGCCGCCACCUCUACCUGUUCCCAGGACACCCUCCCACAUGAUGUCACCUCCCCAUCAUCCACGCCAAGUGGAAGCCACUGGACCACAGGAGGUGUGAUAGAGCCUUUGAUCUUCAGGAUGCACGGUUUCUGUUCUGCCCCCUCAGGGAUGUGGGAAUCUCCCAGACUUGUUUCCUGUGCCCAUCAUCUCUGCCUUUGAGUGUGGGACUCCAGGCCAGCUCCUUUUCUGUGAAGCCCUUUGCCUGUAGAGCCAGCCUUGGUUGGACCUAUUGCCAGGAAUGUUUCAGCUGCAGUUGAAGAGCCUGACAAGUGAAGUUGUAAACACAGUGUGGUUAUGGGGAGAGGGCAUAUAAAUUCCCCAUAUUUGUGUUCAGUUCCAGCUUUUGUAGAUGGCACUUUAGUGAUUGCUUUUAUUACAUUAGUUAAGAUGUCUGAGAGACCAUCUCCUAUCUUUUAUUUCAUUCAUAUCCUCCGCCCUUUUUGUCCUAGAGUGAGAGUUUGGAAGGUGUCCAAAUUUAAUGUAGACAUUAUCUUUUGGCUCUGAAGAAGCAAACAUGACUAGAGACGCACCUUGCUGCAGUGUCCAGAAGCGGCCUGUGCGUUCCCUUCAGUACUGCAGCGCCACCCAGUGGAAGGACACUCUUGGCUCGUUUGGGCUCAAGGCACCGCAGCCUGUCAGCCAACAUUGCCUUGCAUUUGUACCUUAUUGAUCUUUGCCCAUGGAAGUCUCAAAGAUCUUUCGUUGGUUGUUUCUCUGAGCUUUGUUACUGAAAUGAGCCUCGUGGGGAGCAUCAGAGAAGGCCAGGAAGAAUGGUGUGUUUCCCUAGACUCUGUAACCACCUCUCUGUCUUUUUCCUUCCUGAGAAACGUCCAUCUCUCUCCCUUACUAUUCCCACUUUCAUUCAAUCAACCUGCACUUCAUAUCUAGAUUUCUAGAAAAGCUUCCUAGCUUAUCUCCCUGCUUCAUAUCUCUCCCUUCUUUACCUUCAUUUCAUCCUGUUGGCUGCUGCCACCAAAUCUGUCUAGAAUCCUGCUUUACAGGAUCAUGUAAAUGCUCAAAGAUGUAAUGUAGUUCUUUGUUCCUGCUUUCUCUUUCAGUAUUAAACUCUCCUUUGAUAUUAUGUGGCUUUUAUUUCAGUGCCAUACAUGUUAUUGUUUUCAACCUAGAAACCUUUAUCCCUGCUUAUCUGAAACUUCCCAACUUCCCUGUUCUUUAAGACUUUUUUUUUUUUUUUUUUUUUUUUUGAGACAGAGUCUCGCUCUGUCGCCCAGGCUGGAGGGCAGUGGCACGAUCUCAGCUCACUGCAAGCUCCAACUCCCGGGUUCACGCCAUUCUCCUGCCUCAGCCUUCCAAGUAGCUGGGACUACAGGUGCCCGCCACCGUGCCCGGCUAAUUUUUUUGUAUUUUUAGUAGAGACAGGGUUUCACCAUGUUAGCCGGGAUGGUCUUGAUCUCCUGACCUCAUGAUCCACCCACCUCAGCCUCCCAAAGUGUUGGGAUUACAGGCGUGAGCCACUGCGCCCGGGCAAGACCUUUUUUUAAAAAAAAAAAAAAAAAAACUUCCAUUCUUUCUUCCUCCAGUCUGUUCUCACAUAACAGAGUAGUUUUGGUUUUUAAUUUUUUUUGGUUGUUUGCUGUUUUUUGUUUUUUAAGGUGAGUUCUCACUAUGUUUCUCAGACUGGUCUCGAACUCCUGGCCUCAAGCCAUCUUCCCGCCUCAGCCUCUCAAAUAGCUGGGCUUACAGGCAUGAGCCACCACACCUGGCCAGGAUUUGGUUGUUUAAAUAUAAAUCUGAUCACCCCCCUGCUUAGAACCCUUCUGCUUUCUAUUACCCCUCAUUUAAAAUGUAAACUCUUCACCUUGGUUUAUGAGAACUGGUUCUUGCCUUCCCCUUGAACCUCAUUAAAUGGUGAUUUCUUGCUAAGCUCCAGCCCGAGUGGUCUCCUCUCAGCUUCUAAUUUUGUGCUCUUUCCUGCCCUUUUCCUGGGCCUUCUCAGCUCUCCACCCCCACCACUCUUGACUCAGGUGGUGUCCUUCUUCCUCAAGUCUUGACAAUUCCCGGGCCCUUCAGUCCCUGAGCAGUCUACUUCUGUGUCUGUCACCACAUCUUGUCUUUUCCCCUCAUUGCAUUUAUUGCAGUUUAUAUAUAUGCUACUUUUACUUGUUCAUUUCUGUCUCCCCUACCAGGCUGUAAAUGAGGGCAGAAACCUUGUUUGUUUUAUUCACCAUCAUGUACCAAGUGCUUGGCACAUAGUGGGCCUUCAUUAAAUGUUUGUUGAAUAAAAGAGGGAAGAAGGCAAGCCAACCUUAGCUACAAUCCUACCUUUUGAUAAAAUGUUCCUUUUGACAAUAUACACGGAUUAUUAUUUGUACUUUGUUUUUCCAUGUGUUUUGCUUUUAUCCACUGGCAUUUUUAGCUCCUUGAAGACAUAUCAUGUGUGAGAUAACUUCCUUCACAUCUCCCAUGGUCCCUAGCAAAAUGCUAGGCCUGUAGUAGUCAAGGUGCUCAAUAAAUAUUUGUUUGGGUGGUUUGUGAGCCUUGCUGCCAAGUCCUGCCUUUGGGUCGACAUAGUAUGGAAGUAUUUGAGAGAGAGAACCUUUCCACUCCCACUGCCAGGAUUUUGUAUUGCCAUCGGGUGCCAAAUAAAUGCUCAUAUUUAUUACUGA